AUACCAGCUGAAGAGCGACAAGCCGCUGGCAGCCGCGGAUCUCACCGCCGCUCAGGGUGAGUCCCGCGGGAGGGGCUGGACUCGGGGCCGGUGGGGACUGAGGCGCCCGUUCGGGUCGGGCGGCUUCGAGGCACUCGGGAAUCGGCCCAGGGUGGGGGGCCCAGGCAGGAAGUGCCUCUUCCUCGCCGCGCUCUUCCCGGGGUCCCAGAGCGGCCGCCCCAGAUCCUUCAGGGUGGGCCCCGGCGCUGGGACCGCGGGCGGACGCGCGGGGCUGUUUGCUCUUUGUGAGGCCUGGCGCGGCGGCCGCCGUCGGCCCGCCCCCGCCGCGCAGCCGGGCGACCGGUGCGACAACAGCCGCAACCCCUCCGCGCGGCGCCCGCGCCUCCGCCCCGUUUCCCCGUCGCGUCCUCCGAGGCCCGCCGCCGAGGCCCACGGCGCCCCCUGGGCGGACGGUCUGGCCGCGACCCCCAACCCGCCGCGCCGCGCCGCGGCUGCCCCGCCCCCACCCGUCGCAUAGUCGGGGGCGCGCCCGGUCUCCGCCCCGAAUCCAAGUCGGAACUUGACCGAGUUGUUUGGGCCGCGAUGACCGCACGGCGUGAACCGUCCUGAGCAGGGCCCACGCCCGGCCCAAGCGGCCCAGCCACCGGGCUGGGGCGGUGUCUCCCUUUGCCCCCUCCCCCCCAUGAACGUCCGCCUCCCCCGCCCUCCUGCCCAGAGGACCCGGGACUGACAGCGCAGGGUGACGGUUGGGCAGCCCGCCGGGUGUCGGGACCAAGAGAGCCCCCCGGCCACCCGCUCAGCUGUUUCCUGCUCGUGUUUGUUGUGCCGAGGGAGGCCCCGCCGCCACCGCCGCCGCCGCGCUCUGCCGCCCCGGUCCCUCCCGAUUGGCCGGCUGGCGUCACGUGGCCUCCAUCAGCUGGGCCGGCGGGGGCGCUCGCGGGCCCCACUGCGGCUGCCGGAGAUCUGUUGGUAAUCUGAGGAUUUUUAUUCUACGUCGUCUUGACAGAUGGAAAACCUGAAGUAACUUCGGGCUAACCUUGUGUUUUUGGAAAAUUAGUAGACUUGGUGGUGAAGAAACUGGGAGGAGUAGGAUAUUAGCUAACUUUGCAUAGCCACAUAUAGAGCGUCGCAGCUGCAUUCCACCAAAGAGGAACCAAAAGGCCUGUGGUGUUCCCAGGGUACAUAUUCAUGCCAGAAGUGAAGUGCUUUGGUGAAUUCGUUUCCUGAAAGUUUAUCGCAUACUUGUACUGGGUUAGGUUUUUAGAACUUCAGCCAUAAAAAUGGGCAGAAUUUUCCUUGAUCAUAUCGGUGGUACCCGUCUGUUUUCUUGUGCAAACUGUGAUACGAUCCUGACCAACCGCUCAGAACUCAUCUCCACUCGUUUCACAGGCGCCACUGGCAGAGCAUUUCUUUUUAACAAGGUAGUUAACCUGCAGUACAGUGAAGUUCAAGAUCGGGUCAUGCUCACUGGCCGCCACAUGGUUCGAGAUGUGAGCUGCAAAAACUGCAAUAGCAAACUGGGAUGGAUCUAUGAGUUUGCCACUGAAGACAGCCAGCGAUAUAAGGAAGGCCGCGUGAUCCUGGAACGUGCUCUAGUUCGAGAGAGUGAGGGCUUUGAGGAGCAUGUACCAUCUGAUAACUCUUGAAGAUACAGAGAGAAAUCCAUCUUUUCCCAGGUCUCCUUCACUGAAAACAAAAAUCUACUUACAUACACUGUCACCUUAGCAUCAGAGUCGGAUUAAUGAACUGCGGAACAAGAGGUUGUGAGAAUCUAAGAUGGAACCUUUCUUUCUUUCUUUCUUUUUUUUUAAAUUUUGUAUUUUCCAUCCAACAGCAGUGUGUAGAGAGAAUAUUAUGCAGAUGCCGUUAAUUUUUUACCCUAUGUUUACAUCUUGAGGCAGCAGAGUCUGUCUGCAGCUAUGUGGUGAGCUAUGUAAGGAAAAAAAUCUGGGCUGUUAGAGUGAAAAAGUGUGUUUUAUGUCAAUUGUGAAAGGAAAAUGUUAGGAGUAUGGUUUUUAAACUUGGGCUUCAUUUUAAACUUUUUUUUUUAAACCCAGUUAUUUCACUUGAUUUGCUAGCUUCAGAGAAGAGAUCCGAAUCUGUGCCCAGCGCUAAAGGCUCAGUGUUAGCAUGGCUUGUGCUGGCCGGUGUGCCAUAUUCUUGUUGGAGAUGAACCGUAGCACCAGAGCCCAUUCUUCCUUGUCAGUCUUGGCCCAAAGAUGUCACCAUUCCUAGUUAUUUGUCACCACAUAAUUGGUGUUGAUUGGAAACUUUUUCUGAGAUGGGACAGAACUGCUGGGUUGUCUUUUUCCAUGUAACUUAAGCAUAGUAAUAUAAAUAAAGUAAUAGUUGGAUGCUUUUGGUCCUGUGUUGCUUUUAAAAACACCUUAUAAAAGAGGAGAGUAUUUGAUAAGCAAUUUUCAUAGUAGUAAAGUUUUUUUUCAUCUCUUAAACUAAAUUGACCAUGCAUAUAAUAUUCUUUGUUUAAAUGAAAGCAUACUGUUGAAACCCGCAGUGUUGCAUUUAGAAAACAGUUGAACAGAAUGUCAAUGUGCAUUCAUGCAAAAAAACAUUUAAUCUGCAUCUGUUUUAGAAAAGGGGGAAAUGAAGCAACUUGUCUAAAAAUACUGCUUUACAAAGCAUUUCAGCCUUUCCCCCUCAGUUUUGCAUUGAUUUUUUGACAAGUCUGUAGAGCCUAAUAGUUUCCAUCAAAGGCCUAGAUCUCUUAUUUAGCAUUUUUUUCAGCUCUUCUCUCAGAAGUUCAGCUGUUGAAACGAAAACUGUACUUUGUACCCUCACAUACAAAGGGAUCAAAUUUGACCUGGUGUUAUUUUAGCCCCAAAUUUAUGACAUUACACAAUAUUAAAAUGUAAAUGUUUCUUUACCCAAACUACUUCUAGAUAUUCUAGUAUUUGCUUCUGGUGGAAUUAAAUGACGGUAAAAUUGGCUAAUUAUUUGAAUGAAUGAAUGGAUGGAUGUUUUGCAUGCUCAAUUUCUAGGUCCUUUGUCUAGAAAGGAAAUUUGCCUCAGUUGAAUUAGUGAAAUAUUUCUGUCGUUGAUAUUAAAAGUGACUUCUGAGUACAGUUAAGUUCCUCCUAUUUGCCACUGGGCUGUUGGUUAGAAGCAUAGGUAACUGAUUAAGUAGGUAUGAUACUGCAUUUGAAAUAAGUGGACACAAACUAUCCUUUCUCCACCAUGGACUCAAUCUGAGAACAACAGCAUUCAUUUCCAUUCAUUUCCAUACUGGCUUUUGAUUAUAUGCAGAUUCCUAGUAGCAUGCCUUACCUACAGCACUAUGUGCAUUUGCUGUCACAAUAAAGUAUAUUUUGUCUUGCA